GUGAAAUCUUUAACUUCCUUGAAUUCGACCACCUCCUUCUCCCUACGGAUUGAACAACCGGGGAAUAGAAAAAUCGCUUAGUUUGGUGUGGGGCGGUUAUUUUGAGUUAACAUCUUUUUUUCCCUUGGGCUUAGCUAUCUAAGAACUCUACCUGCCUCAAAAGGUAGAGGAGCGUCCAUCCCACGGGCUACCACGGUGACCCCUUCCAGUGAAAAUAGGAAAAGAAUUCAAAAUACAAAAUGAACUUUAAAAGGGUGUGUGUGUGAACUAUCUUCUGUGUCAAUUAGCCUUAUGAAGACGUAGGCAACAGGACUGGUCACGUGUUGUUUAUACUUGAAUCUGUACGUCGGGCUCACAGCAUUUAGGCAUUGAGAAACGAAACCCUAUCAACGCUGUGCACUGACCAAAAUGAUAUUUUCUUUUAUCGAGGCAACUAAUUAACAGGGAUCUUCCCCCUCUUCCCUCUGAGUUGUACAUUUUUGCCGAAUUUGAGUAGUAUGGGUCUUAGAUCUCUUGUAAUUGUGAAUGACUUAGUUUGGUUAACCUUUGAUAAGGACUUUUUUCCCCGACUUUUUUUUCUGAUCUAAAGUAAAUUGAAAAGCCAGUCGGUUGUUUUCUAAUCUCGAUGAUGUGGAAUUUUGCUAUUCUUUCCAUCUGGCUGAUAACUAAUGUUAAGCUUACUUCUUCACUUUGAUCUUCUGUUGGCUUAGUGCUUAUUGAAGCCCUUUUAGGUUGGGGCCUGGAAUCCUCAAGAGGUUGUUUUCUGUCAGUAACUCGGGAGUGCUGUGGCCUUUCUGUUGAGCAUGCUCUGUAGUCCACACGUUUCCACAUAGUGGUGUUUUCUUUGCACAGUUUUGUAGGAAGACUUUAUGAGUGCUGUAACUCUACUCCCCUUUUUGCUCUCAUAAGAAGCAUUAUAAAAUGUUAACUUAUGUUAUUCACAGGGCAUGUAAGGAGAUGGGAAGGAAUAGAGGUAUCAGUACAUAUGUCCAUGCUCCUCCAUAGAUUUUCUUCUGGUUGGUAGAAAUGUUGAGCUUUUCAUUCCUAAACAUUGAACAUUGAAUGUGCAAGGUGAAUUCCUAGAAACUUGAAUGCAGUCUUAAAAGCCAAAUGAUAACAUUGGUUUUUCCAAAAAUGUUACACAUUUAGAAAAGAGUCCCCCUUCCCCUCUUCUCUUUGCCCACAUUCCUAAGACAAGUAAGGCCAGGAAAAAGGAUUGAUCCUGGUGUCAUAAAAUAUGAGUGAAAAUUUCAAAGUCCUUUGUUAGCUUAAUCUUUUCAGUUUUGUAGAGUUUGAAUAGACCAACUGAUACUUAAAUAACUCAGUAUUAGAAAUGACAGGUUGAUCUCAAGUAAUUUUUUUUUGAGACAGAGUCUCUUGUCACUCAGGCUGGUGUGCAGUGUCACGAUCUCGGCUCACUGCAACCUCCGCCUUCAGGGUUCAAGUGAUUCUCCUGCUUCAGCCUCCUGAGUAGCUGGGAUUACAGGCGCGCCCCACCAGGCCUGGCUAAUUUUUGUAUUUUUAGUAGAGAUGAGGGUUCACCAUGUUGGUCAGGCUGGUCUCGAGCUCCUGACCUCGUGAUCCCCUCACCUCGGCCUUCCAAAGUGCUGGGAUUACAGGCGUGAGCUACCGCAGACGGCCGAUCUCAAGUAAUUUUUUUUUUUUUUUUAAGAGACGGAGUCUCGCUGUGUCGCCCAGGCUGGAGUGCGGUGGCGCGAUCUUGGCUCACUGCAAGCUCCGCCUCCCGGGUUCACGCCAUUCUCCUGCCUCAGCUUCCUGAGUAGCCCACGCUGGGCUAAUUUUUGUAUUUUUAGUAGAGAUGGGGUUUCACCGUGUUAGCCAGGAUGGUCUCGAUCUCCUGACCUGGUGAUCUGCCCGCCUCGGCCUCCCAAAGUGCUGGGAUUUACUGGUGUGAGCCAUUGCGCCUGGCCACUUUUCCCCAGCUUUCUUAAGUCACUGCGCAGAGGUGAGAGGAAAAAGGAAAAGUGAUACCCAAAAUAAAAGGACAUAGUAUACUCAUAUGAUUAUUGUAUCGCAGGUGGCAUUGCCUUUAUGUUCUUGUUUAAUUUUUUAAAACUGAGAUAACUUGUUAAUCAUAAUAUAGUACAGCUUGUACUUGUGACCUGAAUUUACUUAGGGUGCUGAGCGUAAUUAACCUGAUGGAGCCAUGUCAUCUAUCAGUAUGGUUGGAAAGAGAGAACAGACCUAAGCUCUGAAUGUGACUAGAGCAGAGGAAGCUAUGCUGAAAUUUUUUUUUUUUUUUUUUUGGGACGGAGUCUCGCUGUGUCGCCCAGGCUGGAGUGCAGUGAUGCGAUCUCGGCUCACUGCAAACAGAAUGAAAAAAGAGAACUGUAUUUGGAGUGCUGAGACCUUGAAAUUGGAAUCUUCGGACCUGGUGAAGGUGUGGAAUCCAGGAGUUGGGAAAGUGCUGCAAAAGCUUCACCAGUGGUUACUCCACAGGAUCCGCUGAACAUAGGAUGUUGCCACAAAAUCUACCUCGUGUAUUUUUCUCUUUCACUCAUGAGCUGCACAAUUGCAGAUUUGAGCACAAUGUCUGCAGACUGUGUUGAAAAACUCUGAAGAACCUAAUUAACACAGGAUGACCUAGGAGUGAUUCUAAGUCUGUGUAACAAGAUAUUACUCAUUAGUGAAUGUGUCAGUCUUGGUACUGAAUGCUGCAGAUAACAGCAAGUAGGUUCUCCUUUAUUUCUGAAGUAUUCACUUGACCUUCCAUCAGUAAGACGGACUUUUCUAAUCUGUUCCUGGAGAUAUUAAUGGAAUACAGUCAUGUCCACUCAAGACGAGAGGCAGAUCAAUACUGAAUAUGCUGUGUCAUUGUUGGAACAGUUGAAACUGUUUUAUGAACAGCAGUUGUUUACUGACAUAGUGUUAAUUGUUGAGGGCACUGAAUUCCCUUGUCAUAAGAUGGUUCUUGCAACAUGUAGCUCUUAUUUCAGGGCCAUGUUUAUGAGUGGACUAAGUGAAAGCAAACAAACCCAUGUACACCUGAGGAAUGUCGAUGCUGCCACCUUACAGAUAAUAAUAACUUAUGCAUACACGGGUAACUUGGCAAUGAAUGACAGCACUGUAGAACAGCUUUAUGAAACAGCUUGCUUCCUACAGGUAGAAGAUGUGUUACAACGUUGUCGAGAAUAUUUAAUUAAAAAAAUAAAUGCAGAGAAUUGUGUACGAUUGUUGAGUUUUGCUGAUCUCUUCAGUUGUGAGGAAUUAAAACAGAGUGCUAAAAGAAUGGUGGAGCACAAGUUCACUGCUGUGUAUCAUCAGGACGCGUUCAUGCAGCUGUCACAUGACCUACUGAUAGAUAUUCUCAGUAGUGACAAUUUAAAUGUAGAAAAGGAAGAAACCGUUCGAGAAGCUGCUAUGCUGUGGCUAGAGUAUAACACAGAAUCACGAUCCCAGUAUUUGUCUUCUGUUCUUAGCCAAAUCAGAAUUGAUGCACUUUCAGAAGUAACACAGAGAGCUUGGUUUCAAGGUCUGCCACCCAAUGAUAAGUCAGUGGUGGUUCAAGGUCUGUAUAAGUCCAUGCCCAAGUUUUUCAAACCAAGACUUGGGAUGACUAAAGAGGAAAUGAUGAUUUUCAUUGAAGCAUCUUCAGAAAAUCCUUGUAGUCUUUACUCUUCUGUCUGUUACAGCCCCCAAGCAGAAAAAGUUUACAAGUUAUGUAGCCCACCAGCUGAUUUGCAUAAGGUUGGGACCGUUGUAACUCCUGAUAAUGAUAUCUACAUAGCAGGGGGUCAAGUUCCUCUGAAAAACACAAAAACAAAUCACAGUAAAACAAGCAAACUUCAGACUGCCUUCAGAACUGUGAAUUGCUUUUAUUGGUUUGAUGCACAGCAAAAUACCUGGUUUCCAAAGACCCCAAUGCUUUUUGUCCGCAUAAAGCCAUCUUUGGUUUGCUGUGAAGGCUAUAUCUAUGCAAUUGGAGGAGAUAGCGUAGGUGGAGAACUUAAUCGGAGGACCGUAGAAAGAUACGACACUGAGAAAGAUGAGUGGACGAUGGUAAGCCCUUUACCUUGUGCUUGGCAAUGGAGUGCAGCAGUUGUGGUUCAUGACUGCAUUUAUGUGAUGACACUGAACCUCAUGUACUGUUAUUUUCCAAGGUCUGACUCAUGGGUAGAAAUGGCCAUGAGACAGACUAGUAGGUCCUUUGCUUCAGCUGCAGCUUUUGGUGAUAAAAUUUUCUAUAUUGGAGGGUUGCAUAUUGCUACCAAUUCCGGCAUAAGACUCCCCUCUGGCACUGUAGAUGGGUCUUCAGUAACUGUGGAAAUUUAUGAUGUGAAUAAAAAUGAGUGGAAAAUGGCAGCCAACAUCCCUGCUAAGAGGUACUCUGACCCCUGUGUUAGAGCUGUUGUGAUCUCAAAUUCUCUAUGUGUGUUUAUGCGAGAAACCCACUUAAAUGAGCGAGCUAAAUACGUCACCUACCAAUAUGACCUGGAACUUGACCGGUGGUCUCUGCGGCAGCAUAUAUCUGAACGUGUACUGUGGGACUUGGGGAGAGAUUUUCGAUGCACUGUGGGGAAACUCUAUCCAUCCUGCCUUGAAGAGUCUCCAUGGAAACCACCAACUUAUCUUUUUUCAACGGAUGGGACAGAAGAGUUUGAACUGGAUGGAGAAAUGGUUGCACUACCACCUGUAUAGUGGGGAAGUUCAGGGAGUGCACGCCUGAGUUAUGUGCUUUGUCAUUUUCUUUGCUAAACAAAAGAGGCUAUGAAAGAACUAAAUAUGAGUACAUAAAAUUCUAUCUUUGAUAAAUUUUAUUUUUAUGCCCUACUUAAUAUUUGCAUCAGUAUAAUAUAUAUCAGUGAGUCUUACAGAAAGAUAUGCUUCCAUAAUAUGAAAUAGAUUAUUCAAUAAUUGAGAAACUUUAUGUGUAAUCAUGAGAGUAUAAGAAUCUGGAUUAUCUAACAUUGUUAGCCCUGUGUAUGUACAGUUCAAAAAGUUCAUUUAUAAAAGUAGUUUCCUGUUCCUAGUGUGAUGUAUCACAAAUUGUGCUGAGGUUAUUUUAGUAUGUGUGUUUCAUUCCCGUGCUUCUGUUCUGAAGUCCUGGAAUACAGUUUUCAGUGUAAUUAAUUCAACUGCACUUAACACUAAUGUCCGUGUUGGUAUAGAAAUGUCUAAAUCCUAUACUCUAGUUGAGGAAGAUCUUCCAUAAUUUUAUGGUAUUACACAGGGAAAGCUAUGACUGCAGGAUCAGUCUAACUAUACUAUUAGGUGCAUGUAUUCUCUUUUCACUAACUUAUACUUGUCUAUCUAGAAUACAGGUCUUCCAGUCAGCUGGUCAUUUACCAGGUGUGGACUUAAGUUGCUAGGCUUGCAGUAAGAAUUGCCAGCCACUCAUUGUGCGGGUCUGCGUGGAGCUUUAAUCAGAAAAAGCCUCCACUUUCUGUAUUAUGUUAACAUUGGCUCAUGCAUAUAACUAUCUGCUGCUGAUGUAGUUCUCCAUCUUCAAGAUUUAGAGUGGGUUAACCAGGUCAUUACAUCUUAAUUUAAUAACAAGCAUUACUGUAGAGUGAUUGUGUAUAGAUCUGUUAGCUGUCAGGGUGUGUUUUUUUUAACCUGUUGUGUGCGUGUGGGGGUUAGGAUUAGUAAGGUGAACUGUUCAGGAAUUCUCUGCACUAGCUGUGCAGAAGAGCAGAUAACUAGCGCUGCUCUGGCAUUAAUCCCAGGAACCACUAGCAGUAGUGGGGCGCCGCCAAUCUAACAUGAGCACAGGUGCUUCAUGACAAACAUUACUAGCAUGUUCAACUGCACCAUGUUCUGGCACUGUAUUUUGAAUGACAUUAAUUUAUUAAAUAAAUUGUAUAUAUUCAA